AGCCGCCUGCAUCUGUAUCCAGCGCCAGGUCCCGCCAGUCCCAGCUGCGCGCGCCCCCCAGUCCCGCACCCGUUCGGCCCAGGCUAAGUUAGCCCUCACCAUGCCGGUCAAAGGAGGCACCAAGUGCAUCAAAUACCUGCUGUUCGGAUUUAACUUCAUCUUCUGGCUUGCCGGGAUUGCUGUCCUUGCCAUUGGACUAUGGCUCCGAUUCGACUCUCAGACCAAGAGCAUCUUCGAGCAAGAAACUAAUAAUAAUAAUUCCAGCUUCUACACAGGAGUCUAUAUUCUGAUCGGAGCCGGCGCCCUCAUGAUGCUGGUGGGCUUCCUGGGCUGCUGCGGGGCUGUGCAGGAGUCCCAGUGCAUGCUGGGACUGUUCUUCGGCUUCCUCUUGGUGAUAUUCGCCAUUGAAAUAGCUGCGGCCAUCUGGGGAUAUUCCCACAAGGAUGAGGUGAUUAAGGAAGUCCAGGAGUUUUACAAGGACACCUACAACAAGCUGAAAACCAAGGAUGAGCCCCAGCGGGAAACGCUGAAAGCCAUCCACUAUGCGGUAUGUCGCCUUGGCAAAGACACCCUCCUGCGCUUUCUCCGGAUUGUGUCUGCACACAGGGUGCUGACUGCACCAGACCAGUGCAAACAUUCUAAUCGUCUUCUUACAAUUUGUUUCUCUCAUCCCCAUCCCUGCCUUCUCGCUGUAGUUGAACUGCUGUGGUUUGGCUGGGGGCGUGGAACAGUUUAUCUCAGACAUCUGCCCCAAGAAGGACGUACUCGAAACCUUCACCGUGAAGGUAAACUCAGACCAGGAUCCUGGUGUCCCUGCCCCCAUUGCUCUGGACAAACCCUGCAAGCAUGAAAGUGACAGCAGCCAAGUGCUGCUUCAGCAAGACCCGUUCUGCCUGUGAAAGGGCCCCAGGGCACCCAUCUCUUUCUCUCCCACUUUGGGCCCUCUGUUUACUCAAGGGCAAUAAAACAAAGGCCGGACCAGGGGAAUGACAAGUGUUCUGGCACCGCCCACUGCUGCCAGCCCGGAAGCUCUCAAGGGCAGGCGUGCUUCUGAGUCUUGGACUCCCACUCUGACUUUGUCAGUGGCUCCUGUCUGUAAGCCAGAGUUAAUGUCCAACUCCAGAAUAGUAAAAGGUGACCUUACAACCAUGUCAGAAAUAGACCCCCAAGCAGGGCCUGUCCCUCCUCCUUCCCUGACGUCCUGCCCAGAUUUUAGGGAUCCACUAGCAUAGCCAUCCCUUUGUUCCCCUUUCCAUCCACCAGCCAGAACUUCUCUUAUCCCCGAACACUCCUGUCCCCAGCCCACCCUCUGCCCACCAGUUCUCCCGGGUGAGACGGGGGCCAUGGGAGGGAGGAGGUGCCCUGGGAGGAAGGAUUGUGUGUGACC